ACUCACCUCCGCACUGCAGCCAAGGGAGGCCCGCCCUGGCGUGGGCUGCUGCCUGUGGCUUUGGGCAGGCAGGAGCGAAAGGGCCAGGGGUUGCCUGUCCUCCCCCACCCUGUUGAGGCCUUCCUCCCCCUCUGCUGAGCCUCGGUUAAUUAUAACUCUGACCUAAGUGCCCUGUGACGUCAAGCCCGGGCCAGCCCUGCCCAGGAGACCCAGCAACCAGGUCCAUGUCUCAGCCAUGCUCCCCACGGAGGUCCCCCAAUCCCACCCGGGCCCCUCAGCGUUGCUUCUGCUGCAGCUGUUGCUGCCCCCCACAUCUGCCUUCUUCCCCAACAUCUGGAGCCUGCUGGCUGCCCCUGGCUCCAUCACCCACCAAGACCUAACUGAGGAGGCAGCGCUCAACGUCACCCUGCAGCUCUUCCUGGAGCAGCCACCCCCAGGCCGCCCCCCUCUUCGUCUUGAGGACUUCCUGGGUCGAACACUCCUUGCUGAUGACCUCUUUGCCGCCUACUUUGGACCUGGUUCUUCUCGGCGGUUCCGAGCAGCCUUAGGUGAGGUGUCUCGUGCCAAUGCAGCCCAGGACUUCCUGCCAACUUCCAGGAAUGACCCCGACCUGCACUUUGAUGCUGAGCGACUGGGUCAGGGACGCGCGCGCCUGGUAGGGGCUCUGCGGGAGACCGUGGUGGCAGCCAGGGCCCUUGACCACACCCUGGCUCGCCAGCGCCUCGGGGCUGCACUUCAUGCCCUGCAGGAUUUCUACAGUCAUAGCAACUGGGUGGAGCUGGGCGAGCAGCAGCCACACCCUCACCUCCUCUGGCCAAGGCAGGAGCUCCAGAACCUGGCACAAGUGGCCGAUCCUACCUGCUCCGAUUGCGAGGAGUUGAGCUGCCCCAGGAAUUGGCUGGGCUUCACACUCCUCACCUCUGGCUACUUUGGAACUCAUCCCCCGAAACCUCCAGGGAAAUGUAGCCACGGGGGCCAUUUUGACCGGAGCAGCUCCCAGCCACCGAGGGGAGGCAUCAACAAGGACAGCACAUCCCCAGGCUUCUCCCCUCACCACAUGCUGCACCUCCAGGCUGCAAAACUGGCCCUUCUAGCCUCCAUCCAGGCCUUCAGCCUUCUGCGAAGCCGCCUGGGAGACAGGGAUUUCUCCAGGCUGCUGGACAUCACCCCAGCCUCCAGCCUGAGCUUUGUCCUGGACACCACGGGCAGCAUGGGUGAGGAGAUCAACGCUGCCAAAAUCCAGGCUCGCCACCUUGUGGAGCAGCGGAGAGGCAGCCCCAUGGAGCCUGUCCACUAUGUCCUGGUGCCUUUUCAUGACCCAGGGUUCGGCCCUGUCUUUACAACCAGUGACCCUGACAGCUUCUGGCAACAGCUUAAUGAGAUCCAUGCCUUGGGGGGUGGAGACGAGCCUGAGAUGUGCCUGUCAGCCCUGCAGCUGGCCCUGCUGCACACACCUCCACUCUCAGAUAUCUUUGUCUUCACGGAUGCCUCCCCCAAGGAUGCCUUUCUCACCAACCAGGUGGAAUCCCUGACUCAGGAGCGGCGCUGCCGGGUAACAUUCCUGGUGACUGAAGAUACAUCAAGGGUUCAGGGUCGAGCUCGGCGUGAGAUCUUGUCCCCUCUGCGUUUUGAGCCAUACAAAGCAGUGGCCCUGGCCUCAGGAGGAGAGGUGAUCUUCACCAAAGACCAGCACAUUCGAGACGUGGCAGCCAUUGUUGGGGAGAGCAUGGCUGCCCUGGUGACUCUUCCCCUGGACCCUCCUGUUGUGGUGCCUGGGCAGCCACUUGUGUUCAGCGUGGAUGGGCUGCUCCAGAAGAUCACAGUCCGGAUCCACGGAGACAUCAGCAGCUUCUGGAUCAAGAACCCUGCAGGGGUCUCCCAGGGCCAGGAGGAAGGCGGGGGUCCUCUAGGUCACACUCGCCGCUUUGGGCAGUUCUGGAUGGUGACCAUGGAUGACCCUCCACAGACAGGAACCUGGGAGAUCCAGGUCACAGCUGAGGACACCCCUGGGGUGAGAGUGCAAGCCCAGACCUCCCUGGACUUCCUCUUCCACUUUGGGAUCCCCAUGGAGGAUGGACCCCACCCUGGCCUCUACCCCCUGACUCAGCCAGUUGCAGGUCUUCAGACCCAGCUGCUGGUAGAAGUGACAGGGUUGGGUUCCAGAGCCAAUCCUGGGGAUCCUCAGCCGCAUUUCUCCCACGUCAUCCUUCGAGGGGUCCCAGAGGGUGCCGAACUAGGCCAGGUGCCCUUGGAGCCCGUGGGACCUCCGGAGCGAGGUCUCCUCGCAGCCUCGCUGUCGCCCACGCUGCUGUCCACCCCUAGACCCUUCUCCCUGGAGCUGAUUGGCCAGGACGCAGCGGGGCGGCGCCUGCACAGGGCUGCCCCUCAGCCUAGCACUGUAGUCCCUGUCCUUCUGGAGCUUAGUGGCCCCUCGGGUUUCUUGGCCCCGGGCAGCAAAGUCCCGCUCAGUCUCCGCAUCGCCAGCUUCUCGGGCCCUCAGGAUCUUGACCUUAGGACUUUCGUCAACCCCAGCUUCUCCCUCACCUCCAACCUCUCCAGGGCUCACCUGGAACUGAAUGAGUCGGCCUGGGGCCGCCUGUGGCUGGAGGUCCCAGAUUCAGCGGCCCCGGAUUCCGUGGUGAUGGUGACUGUGACUGCAGGGGGACGAGAAGCCAACCCAGUACCCCCGACUCAUGCUUUCCUCCGGCUCCUGGUAUCGGCCCCAGCCCCGCAGGACCGGCACACCACCCCUACCGGCUCAUCUGACCCGAUCCUCACCACGGCCACCCCUGCCUUUUCCCCCUUCACAUUGGUGACUCAAGGCAGGGCUGGGGCAGGGCUGGCUGCGGGCAGCCCCUGGUGGGGCACAGUUGGAGGGGUGCUGCUUCUGCUAGGCCUGGCCUCCUGGUGACACA